GCUCAGGUUUCCUACCUUCCGGCUGCUUGGGAACUUCUUUCUUGCCCGCCAAGCCCGCAGCCACCCGGGCGCGGCGGGACUCCUAGACCCGGCGCUGCGAUGAAGAGGACCCGCGACGAGGUGGAUGCGACGCUGCAGAUCGCCAAGCUGAAUGCGGCCGAGCUGCUGCCGGCGGUGCACUGCCUGGGCUUCGGCCCUGGGGCCAGCGGCGCUGCAGCCGGCGACUUCUGCCUGCUGGAGCUGGAGCCCACGCUGUGCCAGCAGCUGGAGGAUGGACACAGUCUUGUGAUUCGUGGUGAUAAAGACGAGCAAGCUGUGCUGUGCAGUAAAGACAAAACAUACGACUUGAAGAUAGCAGACACUUCCAAUAUGUUGCUUUUCAUUCCUGGUUGUAAAACUCCGGACCAGUUGAAGAAGGAAGAUUCACACUGUAACAUUAUUCACACUGAGAUCUUUGGUUUUUCUAAUAAUUAUUGGGAAUUAAGAAGACGUAGACCCAAGUUAAAGAAGCUAAAGAAACUUUUGAUGGAAAAUCCAUAUGAAGGACCUGACAGUCAAAAAGAGAAGGAUUCAAAUAGCUCAAAAUAUACAACUGAAGAUUUGCUUGAUCAAAUUCAGGCAAGUGAGGAAGAAAUAAUGACCCAAUUACAAGUUCUAAAUGCCUGUAAGAUUGGAGGUUAUUGGAGGAUUCUUGAAUUUGAUUAUGAGAUGAAACUUCUGAAUCAUGUAACUCAGCUUGUGGAUUCUGAAUCAUGGUCUUUUGGUAAAGUUCCUUUGAACACAUGCCUUCAGGAACUCGGACCAUUGGAGCCAGAGGAAAUGAUAGAACACUGUCUUAAAUGUUAUGGGAAGAAAUAUGUAGAUGAAGGCGAAGUUUAUUUUGAGUUGGAUGCUGAUAAAAUAUGUAGAGCAGCAGCACGAAUGCUACUUCAGAAUGCGGUGAAAUUCAAUCUCGCUGAGUUUCAAGAAGUGUGGCAGCAGAGUGUUCCUGAAGGAAUGGUAACUAGUCUUGAUCAGCUUAAGGGUUUAGCGCUGGUGGAUAGACACUCGAGACCAGAAAUCAUAUUUUUGCUGAAAGUAGAUGAUUUACCUGAGGAUAAUCAGGAACGUUUUAAUAGCCUUUUCUCUCUAAGGGAGAAGUGGACAGAAGAAGAUAUUGCUCCAUAUAUUCAAGAUUUGUGUGGAGAGAAGCAAACCAUAGGUGCAUUACUCACUAAAUAUUCUCAUUCUUCGAUGCAAAAUGGUGUUAAAGUUUAUAAUUCGAGAAGACCCAUUUCUUAAAAGAACAACGGUCUUUUCUUCAGGACUCAAGUUGCUUUAUAAAGUUGCUGGAUAGAAGAAAAAUAACUUGUACUUUUAUUUCUGACUUUUAGAAACCUAGUCUUCUAAGGCAUUUUUCUCCUCAUCUUAAGCAUUUUGAAACUACUGUUAUUUCUUAAAUGUUAUAGGAUGUAGCUUUAAAAUUAUAUUUGUACUAUGUACACAGUGUAAACAAGGACAAAAGAAUUCUUUCCUAUAUUAUGUCUGAGGUCUCUAUGAUUUAUUUAAAGUUUGGCUUUUUAUAUUUAAAAUGUCAUUUCUUUACUUAGGAUUUGAUGUUCUAAUCAUUAAUACACUUAAGUUUUCCAGAGAACUAAAUAGUAAUAGUUUCAUAGAAGAGAACUAUUUAUUCACUUAAAUAUCAUUUCUCAAGUGAGUGAGUUCCCCUCUACUUUUAGCCUUCCACCCAAACUGGAAGCCUCUAGGUGCUAUCAAUUAUUUAUAUCCAUCGUUUACAUCCAUGAAAUUGGCUGAAUAAUUACUCCUCUGCCUGGCGUAGACAUGCGCUUUGGGAAAAAAACGAGUUUAUAAUCCUAUAAUGAAGAAUACUGGCACAGGCAAUGCUCACUCGAAAACUUCAAGUAAUUUCUAGUUGGUUUUGGAAUGCUUGAUAAAGUUCCUUUACAGCUUUAUUUUCCUGAUUUGUUUUGGUUUAGAUCAAAGUUCAAAUUAAUUUUAACUUAGCUAAUGAACUCAUCACCAGGACAGUUGGAGGGGGUAGGCCGAGGUUAAAUGGUCCACGUUUCAAAAAUGUUAAUGGCUAAUCCAUAAUUAAAGAAGGUUUAACUGUUACUGAAGUUUACAAGUUUUAUUGUCAUGAACAUGAAAUACAAACACGAUGGCUUCGAAAUGUCUUUCAAUAAAUGUUUCUGCAUUUA